GCCCCGGCAGCCGCGCCCUGCGUGGCGGAAGCUCACAAUCAGCCCGGUCCCUCCGGCUUCCACCCCGCCCCCUGCGCUCACCUGCCCGCGCGCUCGCCUUCCGGGGACCCGGGGCCCAUGGACACAUACACCCAGCCCUGCUGUCCCGCGCGCCAGCUCACCAGCCCUACCCAAGGGACAUCAUUCACGCCUGGGCGCCUCCGCCGGGCUCCGGGAGCCCAAGGUCGCGGCUGGGCCAGCGCUGAGCGUCAGAGGACGAGAGCAGGGGCCUCCCCGGUCGCCCCAGCAGGCCCAGGCACAUAGGUGCCCAGAGAUCCCUGGCUUCUGAUCGCCCGGAAGACUAAGAGUCCCAUGAAGUGGGCACCAUUGCUAUUGCCAGUUCACAGAUGCAGAAACUGAGGUAAAAACUAGCUUUAGUUUUGGUCCAGAAAGCAUUUUCAAGGAGCUGGUCAAGCAUGGCUUUAGCAGAUAAGAGACUUGAGAACUUACAGAUCUACAAAGUUCUUCAAUGUGUGCGGAACAAAGACAAGAAGCAGAUAGAGAAGCUGACCAAGCUUGGAUACCCUGAACUAAUCAAUUAUACAGAACCCAUUAAUGGACUUAGUGCUUUGCACUUAGCCUCAGUUUCCAAUGAUAUUGAUAUGGUCAGCUUUCUCCUUGACCUUGGUGCUCACCCUGAUGUGCAAGACCGAAUGGGCUGUACUCCCACAAUGAGGGCUGCAGAACUGGGCCAUGAAUUGUCAAUGGAAAUAUUAGCAAAGGCAAAGGCUGAUAUGACUAUAGUUGAUAAUGAAGGAAAAGGUAAAAAUCCCGACAUCCUCUCCAGCAGAUUGCAAUUCAUUUUGUAGCCAGAAAGCAAUAACAUGGACUCUUUUUGUUUUCCAACUUUAGAAGUGAAUUACUUAUGGUUUUAAGGGAAAGGCUAAAUUCUCACUCCUAUACCUAAACCUACUGUCUCCUCAUACUUUGAAAAUGAGAUAGCUAUAUCUUAGGGAAAUCAUUUAUGAGAGCUUGCUCAUAUACUUAGAUUAAUUUGUGUUUGGUGGUUUCUUUUAAAUGAGGAGAAUUUUGAACAUUAUACACACUGAUUAUUCAUUAUAAAUUAUAAACUCUUCUUUAAAACAAAGAUGAAGUAGAGCAUUUCUUAUUCUUUUUUACAUUUUAGAAUUUCAGGCAGUACUACACCUAGGACUCCAAAAGGAUUUUGACCCCCUCAAUAGCAGUCUGAUGUAGGAAGGACUUGCACUUGGAAACUUGAAAGGACUAAAGUCAAUUCUGGCAUAAACUCCAACUUUCUAGGAUCAUUUAAAAAUGUAUUUGGAAAUACAACUUCAAACUUUAGACAUGACCUUUCAACAAUGAUUCAGAUCAAACAACUGCACUUCCACACCGUUAAUCCCAUCAUCUCAAGACCAUGGUCUGAGGACUUCUUGCCCAAAUAACUUAAGGUUCAGGCAAGAAUUGACACAGCCUCAUAAAAAUAACUGAGAUAAUUACCAAUAAGCUUAAUGUAAACUGAUAGGUUUGAGCAGUUGUCCUGAGUUUCUGCAGAUACAAGGCCAUUAACAUCAGCUCUGCAAUCGAGAAAUGAAUCUCAUUUGAUAAUGUGAAUAUUUACUGACAAGAGCAAAAUCUACUUUUCUAACUCUCUCCAGACUUGGUGUUUGAUAUGAUUACUUGCUUAGAACAAAAGAGGACAAAGAAAAGGGAUAAUUACAUAUUUAAUUGUACCACGUAAGAAAAUAAACUUCAGAUGCAUUCAGGGGCCAGAUGUACUUUGAAAUGCUAAAUCCUGAAAAAACGGUAUCCUCUCAAAGCUCUAUAGUAUACCAUUUCCCAAAGUGUGUUCCAUGGACCACUGAAUUGCCAGGAUGUUGAGAAGUACUACAGGCAAAAUUGGUUCCACGGUCGCAUUCAUUAGAGACACAUUUUAGGCAUUUAUCUUUCACAUUGUUGGCUCAAAAAUGGUGACAUUUUCCAUAUUUAUUUGACCACAAAAUAAUUUUUUUUAAUGACAUCUUAUAUGCCUGGAGUUUUGUGGACUAACCUUUGGGAAACACUAUAAUAGAGAAACGUUUAACUUACUGAGUUUGAAACAGAUACAAAUCACAAAGAAAAAAGAAAUUCUAUAGUGUAACAAUGUAAAAGUGUAAAUUUUUUUUAAAAAAUCAAGGUAAAAUUGGAAACAAGGUCAAGUAAAUACUUGCAGCAAAUGCAACAGGCAUAUGGCUAAAGGAAACAAAUCUCAUGGGCAGAACUGAAACUAUAAAAGGAAACAAAUGUAAAAUCUUGUUUCACACAUAAGCUUGUUAGGAUGGCUGCCUGCAGCCCUCACUCUGCAUAACCCAAGGUAGUGCCCAUUGUACAGAGUACAUUGUCUCUUCCCACAUCAACAAGGCUCACUCAGCUUGCACAUCCCUCAGUUUGGCUGCCAGUGGCCAAAGUGCUUUGCUUAUUCCACAGUACCCUCUCUGUCAUUGACAUCCUAUUUUCUGGUGACUCAUGUUUGACUCACUGUACAUCGUUCCUAAAGGAUAAGCAAACAUUUAAAUGGCUAAGUGGGUCUUUAGGAUGUGAGACAUGCCCUAGGCCUAAGCGGCACUUUCUCUUGGAACAGUUUUACAGAAUAUGGAGAAGGUAAAGCUCUAAGCCAAUACAUUCUUUCUUGUAUGUUGUCCUAGGGAAUUAAUUACAAUGUGGAAUCAUUCUCCUUAAAAGUUAAGCUAUAAUAGUUCCUUAUAGCACCCAUUCCCAUUCCAUUGGUUUUUGCAUUUACAGGCAUGUGUACUCAGUCCUCAAUGCCGUAUGCCAGUUCUAUGAUAAGGUGUUUUGUUUUACUGCAUUUUACCGACUAAGCGGCAUUAUCGCUGUGCUCUGAUCGCCCUUGAACAUGGUGCAGAUGUCAACAAUUCUACCUAUGAAGGAAAGCCAAUAUUCCUUAGAGCUUGUGAAGAUGCACAUGAUGUUAAAGAUGUGUGCCUGACAUUUUUGGAAAAAGGAGCCAAUCCUAAUGCAAUCAACUCAUCCACAGGCCGCACAGCUUUAAUGGAAGCGUCAAGAGAAGGGGUAGUGGAAAUAGUUCGAGGCAUAUUGGAAAGAGGAGGUGAAGUGAAUGCAUUUGACAACGACAGGCAUCACGCUGCUCAUUUUGCUGCUAAAGGAGGCUUUUUCGAUAUAUUGAAGCUUCUUUUUGCCUACAAUGGAGACGUGGGGCUGAUUUCGAUAAAUGGGAACACACCACUUCAUUAUGCUGCCAUGGGUGGUUUUGCAGACUGCUGUAAAUAUAUAGCUCAGCGAGGAUGUGACCUGAAAUGGAAGAAUUUAGAUCAUAAAACGCCCAGGGCUGUGGCUAAGGAAGGCGGCUUCAAAGCAGCAAGCAAAGAAAUACGCCGAGCAGAGAGAAUCGCUAAUAAACUAGCCAGGCCAGGAGCCAAAAAUCCAAAUCCACUGUGGGCCCUUAGACUGCACGAUUGGUCCGUAGAACGUGAGGCUUUCCUCCGGGAAGCCUUUGCGGUUUUAGACAGGGGUGAUGGAAGCAUCAGCAAGAACGACUUCGUGAUGGUGUUGGAGGAAAGGCAGGAUUAUGCAAGCUCAGAACAGCUGGCUGCCAUCGCUCACCUUCAUGAGAAAACCCGGGGAGGAGGGGUCAAUAUUAAUGAAUUCUUUAAAGGAACCAGAUAUUUAAACAAGUCUUUUGUCUUAGGAUCGUAUGGACCUAAGAAAAAGGAAAAAGGGAUGGGCAAAAAAGGAAAGAAAGGGAAAUUUGUCUUACCCCUUCCAAUCUGUGUCAUUCCUGAGUACGCGUUUCCACGCCGGCAGGAUGGUGGGCCACCGUAUUACAUGAUUGAGACCUACAAGAAUGUCACUGAUAGCAGCCGGUUUAAUAGAGAUCAUCCCCCAGAACAUCCCAUUCAGGAUGACUCUGUUUGGUACAUUGAUGAUUCAGAGAAGGUAUUUUCAAACAUUAAUAUUAUCACCAAAGCAGGGGAUCUGGCUUCUCUGAAAAAGGCCUUUGAAUCAGGAAUACCUGUGGAUAUGAAGGAUAAUUAUUACAAAACUCCGCUAAUGACGGCGUGUGCAAGUGGAAACAUAGAUGUGGUCAAGUUUCUUCUUGAAAAAGGAGCUAACGUUAAUGCAACAGAUAACUUUCUGUGGACUCCACUUCAUUUUGCAUGCCAUGCAGGCCAACAAGACAUUGUUGAGCUUCUUGUUGAAUCUGGAGCUUUAAUAGAUGCAGCUUCAAUCAACAACUCAACUCCUUUAAAUAGAGCCAUUGAAAGCUGCAGACUGGAUACAGUAAAAUACCUACUUGAUAUUGGUGCUAAAUUCCAGCUGGAAAAUAGAAAAGGGCAUAGUGCCAUGGACGUUGCAAAGGCAUAUGCUGAUUAUAGAAUAAUUGAUCUGAUUAAAGAAAAGCUAGAUAACUUGCCGAAACCAGCAGAAAAUCAAAAACUAAAAGGCAAGACACCUCCUAUACUGAAGACUGAAGGCCCUGAAAUUAAGAAAGAAGAGGAACUGCUGUCAUCAAUUUAUGGUGUACCAACCACAUCAGAGGGAAAGAAAGUACAGAAGGGUAAUGUGGUUCAUCUGAAUUCAUUGAUUACCAGUGGUUAUACUAAGAAAGUGGAUAUCACAUUUAUUCCACGGAGGAUUUGGAGUCCUGAAGCCACAACAGCAGAGCUGAUCAGGAAGAGGGAACUACGGCGAGAGAGGUUUACACAUGAGGUGGACUUCGACGAUUUUAUGAUGCCUUUUCAGAAGAACAUCACAGAGAAAGCUCGAGCACUGGAAGCUGCCUUGAAGACCUAAGUCAUAGCAGUUAUUUCUUGGGGUAAAUGCUUUGAGGCCCAGGGACCAAUCUUUGGAGAAAGUAGAUAUUUCCAUCAAAGCCAAAGCAAUCCAUACACCAAGAACUUGUUACCAAGAAUUUCUUUUUGCUUUAACAACUAUAAAUAUUCUUAGCUGUCUAGAGAAAAGAUGUAUGUUAUUUUGAAAUGAAUGGUAUGUCAUUCUGGAUAAAUCCCCAAGCCCCUUUAUGAAUGUAGUGAAAUACAUGGCAUGUGGGUUAUAAACGUUGCUGUCAAAAGAUUUACCAGGUCUACACCAUUAUGCUUAUUAUUUUUUUAAUUAUCCUUUUUAUUUAUUAAAUAGAGACAGAGUCUCACUAUAUUGCCCCAGCUGGUCUCGAACUCUUGAGCUCAGGCAGUCCUCCCAACUUGGCCGUCGAAAGUGCUGGGAUUAUAGGCAUGAGCUACUGUGCCCAGCCUGCUUAUUGAAGAUACAUUUCUAGUGGAAAUUGAUGAAACAAUUUAGGUUUUGGAAAAAGAAGUAAUAUUUAAUCUUUUAAGGAAGGAGUUUAUUUCUCACAUGCCAUUAUAAACUAUGUGUAUUAGAUACCUUGGGUUGAAUACACUUUUAACAGCCCUAGAUCGAUAGCCCUAGCCCUAGAUAGAUAGCCCUAGCCCUAGAUAGAUAGCUAUUAGGUUGGUGCAAAAGUAAUUGUGGUUUUUGCCAUAACCUUUAAUUGCAGCAAAAACCGCAAUUACUUUUGCUCCAACCUGACAGCUAGGUAUCUAGCUAGCUAGAAAGGCAGAUAGACAGAUAUAUAGAUGAUAGAUAGAUAGAUGAUAGAUAGAUAGAUAGAUGAUAGAUAGAUAGAUAGAUAGAUAGAUAGAUAGAUAGAUAGAGAUUUAUUGCAAAUAAUUGGUUUACAUAAUUUUGGGCCCCAGAUGGUUAAGUGCUAAAUUUGUAGGGUAGGCUAUCAGGAAGUGCAGGCUGGAAACAUGCAGGAGCUGUCCCUGAAGUCCACAAGUGGAAUUUCUUCUUCAUCAUGGAAACCUCAGUUUUGUUCAUACACCUAAAUACUUCAGUAUGUCUUUCCUAAAAUAAAAGGCAUCCAUUUACCUAACCAGAUUACGAUUGUGAAAAUUUCAACUGUUGUUAAAGCGACUGAUGGGAUCAGUUUCACCUAGAUUAUCUAAAGCAGUCUCCUUUACAUAAAGUCAAUGAAUUGUAAAUAUUGGUUGCAUGUACACAAUUCCUUCACCACAACACCUAAGAUUAGUAUUUGAUUGAGUUACUGGGUGCUACAACCUAGCCAAGUUGAGUCAUAAAACUGACCAUCUCUGGAGGUGUACUCUGCAGUAAAAAGCUAGCUGAGGCAUUAUUCACACCAAGAAAUGCAGUGGGUACCGAACAGGAGCUCCAAAAAUAUCCAACGUCUCAUUGACAGAAAGAAGCCACUUUAGAAUCUGCCUUACCAGAAGGCACCAAUUGCAGAUUACAGCUCUGUCAGUCACGUAUGGAUUAAACCCCUUUCCUCUAACCUCCUCCCUCUCUUUCCAACCUUGGAGGGACCUUCCACAGGAGCCAGUUAGGGAGGAGAAGGGAAGAGAGAGAAUGAAGCAGGUAACCAGGCCCACCCCUCUGGAGGAGACAGACCUGAACAGGGGUUGCUUACAAGCAUUGCAUUUGGAUCCCAAGAUUUGCUAUUACAACUAAAUUUUGUCUGUUUUGUAAGGUUUUGGUUGGUUUUUUUGUUCUCUCUUUUCUUUUUGUUUUGACAUAAUUUCAUAUUUAUGGAAAAGUUGCAAUAAUUUGACAAAGAAUUCUUAUAUGCCCUUUACCCAGAUUACCUAAAUGUUAACCACUUACCACAUUUGCUCUAUCUCUUUCUCCCUCUACAUAUAUGCAUAUGUAUGUUUAAUUUUUGUCCCCGAACUAUCUGUGUGUCCGUUGAAGACAUGAUGAAGACAUGAUGUUCUUCACAUGAUGUUUUCAUAUUUGUGUGUCAGUUGAAGACAUGAUGUUUUAAAUAUUUCAUUGUGUAUUUCCUAAAAUCACGAUGUUCUUUUGCAUAACAAUAUUACCAUUGGCAAACUAAGGAAAUUAACACUUAAGUGAACUAUUUAAUCUAUAGACCUUAUUCAGAUUUUGCUAUUUAUCCCAAUAAUUUCCUUUGUACUCCCAGGUCAUGAAAUACAUUCGCUUGCCCCAUCUCUUUAGUCUCUUUUAGUUUAGAACAACCUGUAUUUCUUGUUUGUUUGUUUGUUUGUUUGUUUAUGACAGUAUAUAAGAAGAACACAAGCCACUUUUAUCUUGUAAAAUGUCUCUCAACUUUGGUUUGUCUUAAAUGUCUUCAAGAAUAGAUUCAGGUGAUGCUUUUGGGGCAGCAGUGCUACAGAUGUCAUUGCACCCUUCUCAGUACAUCAUAUCAGGAGGCACAUGAUGUUGAUACCUGAUAUAAACUUUAACUGCAUUUGCAGUUGAGAGAAAUGUAAAUAAAAGUAAAGCUGCAGUAAUAAAUCAUAACUGCAUAAAAUUAACUGUAGUACAUACUGUACAACUGUAAUAAUUUCAUAGCCACCUCCUGUUGCUAUUGUGUUGAGUUCAAUUGUUGUCUUUUCUCAAGCUUACUUUAUUGCACAAAUACAGUAUUUAUAACAUACAAAA